AGUAGCCAAUGAGCGGCCGCCGGUUCCUGCUCCCGGCUCCGUCCGCCGAGUGAGGCCGCGGCCGCGGGGGGUGGGGGGUGGGAGGCCGGGAGGGGGCCGGGACGCCGGGCUCCGGGGCGGGGGCGGGGGGCGCGGGCACCGGCGACCCCGGUGGCGGCGGCGGCGGCCGGGGGAAGCCUCGGGGCCGGUCAUGCGGCUGCGGGGCCCGCGGCCCGGAGCGUCCGCCCAGCCCUGAGCGAGGCCCCGCAGGGCGCCCCCUGCCUCUGAGGAUGAGUCACUGCAGCAGCCGCGCCCUGACCCUGCUGAGCAGCGUGUUUGGUGCGUGUGGCCUGCUCCUGGUAGGCAUCGCGGUCAGCACUGACUACUGGCUGUACAUGGAAGAAGGCACAGUGCUACCGCAGAACCAGACCACCGAGGUCAAGAUGGCCCUGCACGCCGGCCUCUGGCGAGUCUGCUUCUUUGCAGGUCGGGAGAAAGGUCGCUGUGUGGCCUCAGAAUAUUUUCUUGAACCGGAGAUCAAUUUGGUGACGGAAAACACGGAGAAUAUUCUGAAGACAGUGCGCACGGCCACCCCCUUCCCCAUGGUCAGCCUCUUCCUCGUGUUCACGGCCUUCGUCAUCAGCAACAUCGGCCACAUCCGCCCGCAGAGGACCAUUCUGGCUUUUGUCUCUGGCAUCUUCUUCAUACUAUCGGGCCUCUCCUUGGUGGUGGGCUUGGUUCUUUACAUCUCCAGCAUCAACGACGAGGUCAUGAACAGGCCCAGCAGCUCUGAGCAGUAUUUUCAUUAUCGCUACGGGUGGUCUUUUGCCUUCGCCGCUUCCUCCUUCCUACUCAAAGAGGGGGCCGGCGUGAUGUCCGUGUACCUGUUCACCAAGCGCUACGCGGAGGAGGAGAUGUACCGUCCACACCCGGCCUUCUACCGCCCGCGUCUCAGCGACUGCUCCGACUACUCGGGCCAGUUCCUGCAGCCCGAGGCGUGGCGCCGCGGCCGGAGCCCCUCCGACAUCUCCAGCGACGUGUCCAUCCAAAUGACGCAGAACUACCCUCCCGCCAUCAAGUACCCGGACCACCUGCACAUCUCCACCUCGCCCUGCUGAGGCCCGCCCCUCGGAGCUCCCCCUGCCUCCUCCUCCUCCUCGUCUUAGGGGGGUCUCCCUGCAAUGCAGCGCCCCCUUCCGUCCUCGGGACUCCUCGCUCCCACCCGGAGGAGGCUGCGCCAGCUUUAGGCCCCGCCCUCCUCCCAAUGGCUCCGCCCACAGACUCCCUUAUUUCAAUGGCCGCGCCCUCUUUUCCCGACCUCUCCUUUUCAUUGGUCCCUCUCACUCCCAAAUGACUCCUCCCCUUCGUUGGCCCGCCCCUUUCCUCUGGCCCCUCCUCUCCAAGAAAAUUAGCUCCUCCCUCGUUCUCCACCUGCUCUGAGCUGGGAGCAGCCAGAGGCGGUGCAAGCGCCCAGCUCCCCAGAGCUCCCCAACCUCGGACCUCACCGCAGGGGCGCUGGGCUGGAGAGCAGGUUCGGGCAGCCGUCGGGAAUACCGACCAUCCUCUUCUCCCUUCUAACCUGGGCUUCCUUUUUCCCUGCCUAAUCUCACCUCCUGACCUGCUGGGUCCUCCGGUGCAGUGGGAGGGCCGGCUUGCUCCACCCGCAGCCCCGGGGUGGCGUAGGGAAGGGGGCUGGAAGCCACGGGUACGGUUAACCUGGCCCUUCCCUCCCCAUCUCCCCUACUUCCCUGGAAGGUCCCAUUCUUUCUCACCGGCUGGGCUCUUUUCUGCUUCCUGAAGGUUACCUGCCUUUUAGGGGGCUCUUGUCUAAAGGAUCUUCUUGCUUUCUCAGCUAUCCUUGGCUUCUUUUUCGUCUUCCUCCUCCUUUAACUCUUUCUCUCCUUUCCUCCCUUCACCCGUUCGUCCCAAGCCCUUGGGUGCAUCCCGCCCUAGGCGCACACCAGACGGCCAGAAUGGGGACCCUAGGGUGGAGGGAAUUCCCCCACGCCAUCUCCGCACCUGUGCCCGCCUCUCCCCCCUCGAGGCCCCGUCGAGGGAGGGAGGGGCAGUAGCGGGGGUCGACACCCCCCCCAAACCUCUAAGUCUUCCAUUUUCUGGCUCUCCUCCUCAUUGACGUCCCUCUUCCCCCCUCAGAACCCCAACUCUGGCCUCUUUCAAGGGCCCGUCCGCCCCGUUGGACAGAUUUUGGGGGGAGAGGAGGUCACCAGGAACUCGCCCACCCCCCCUUAUUAGGGAAAGAGGGGCGAGGUAGCACAGUGCUGUACACGGAACCAGAAUGGCCCCCGGGGUGGGGGGAGGGGGGCAGGGGAGGGACGGGGGCUUUUAGUUUGCAUCUUAGGUGGGAGGGGGGAGGGGGGACCCGCCGCAGUUAACCUGACUUUACGCAGCGAUUUUUAACGAGGCUGGGGGGAGGGGGGCACUGGGGUGGGGACAGGGUGGGGUGGGGGGCCUGGCUCUGUUAUUUACCGUGUAUCAUAUGUAAAUAUCGACAGAAACUUCAAUAAACUUUAUUUCAAACACGUCUCCGCCUGCCCGGAGGGAAGGGAUUGGAUAGAGGGGGCUUAGUCUGGGUCUCUGCUUCUAGGGUUGCAGGCCUAAAGUACUGCAGAAUGACGUUAGAUGGGUCGUUGUUAAAUGACUUAAUCAUCAUCAUUAUCAACGGCAGCGCUUUAUACUUCAGUCCGUGUAAAGCAUGCAGGACCGUAAAUGAUACUGGUCAGGAUCAAUAAACGCUUUCUCCUGGUAUUAUUAUGA